AGUUCUAUUGUUGCCGAGCGAGUGAGUCACUUCGCAUCUCCGCUCGCCGCCGCUCCGCUCGCUGGACGCCGAAUUGCCCCUCACCCCGCUCCUCGAGACCCCAGCCGCGGCCGGGCCCGGCGCGCGGAGCACCCGGCGGCGGCGCGGAGCAGGGGGCGCCGAGGAGGUGGCAGAGACUGGCUCGGAAACUUGGGGGAGAGGCGGCGAGUUGCGGGAGCCGCCGCGUCGAUCUCGGGCCGCGGCGAGGAACGCGUGGAUUCCGGGACCCGGCGCGGGCACUGAGCCCUCCCGCCCCUUGCUCGCGCCGCGGUGGGAGCGAGUCGGGGUCCUGGAAGUCAUCCCGGCGCCCCCAGCGCUCUUGCGUAAUCUUCCCCAGUACCUCUCUCUGUUCCCUCACACACUUUGGGCCUCGGUGGUCUCUCGCUGAGCCCGUUUCCUCUGCCCUAGGACCUGCUAGAAGUGGCCGAAGAUGAAUCCCCAGCAACAACGCAUGGCCGCUAUAGGGACCGACAAGGAGCUGAGCGACCUACUGGACUUCAGUGCGAUGUUUUCCCCACCUGUUAAUAGUGGGAAAACUAGACCAACUACACUGGGAAGCAGUCAAUUCAGUGGAUCAGGUUUCACAGAUUUGAAUACCAGCCUCCAAUAUUUCAGUAUUGAUGAAAGAGGAGGUACAACAUCUUGGGGAACAAGUGGUCAACCAAGUCCUUCCUAUGAUUCAUCUAGAGGUUUUACAGACAGCCCUCAUUACAGUGAUCACUUGAAUGACAGUCGAUUAGGAGCCCAUGAAGGCUUGUCCCCAACACCUUUCAUGAACUCAAAUCUGAUGGGAAAAACAUCAGAGAGAGGCUCAUUUUCCCUGUACAGCAGAGAUACUGGAUUACCAGGCUGUCAAUCUAGUCUCCUGAGACAAGAUCUGGGGCUUGGGAGCCCAGCACAGCUAUCUUCUUCAGGAAAACCUGGGACAGCAUACUAUUCAUUCUCUGCUACAAGUUCCAGGAGGAGACCACUCCAUGACUCUGCAGCGCUUGAUCCCUUGCAAGCAAAAAAAGUCAGAAAGGUGCCUCCUGGUUUGCCUUCUUCUGUAUAUGCACCAUCCCCAAAUUCAGAUGAUUUCAACCGUGAAUCUCCUAGUUAUCCAUCUCCUAAGCCACCAACCAGUAUGUUCGCUAGCACUUUCUUUAUGCAAGAUGGGACCCACAAUUCUUCUGACCUUUGGAGUUCAUCAAAUGGGAUGAGCCAGCCUGGUUUUGGUGGAAUUCUGGGGACCUCCACUUCCCACAUGUCUCAAUCCAGUAGUUAUGGCAACCUUCAUUCACAUGACCGCUUGAGUUAUCCUCCACACUCAGUUUCACCAACAGACAUAAACACGAGUCUUCCACCAAUGUCCAGCUUUCAUCGCGGCAGUACCAGCAGUUCACCUUACGUUGCUGCCUCACACACUCCUCCCAUCAAUGGAUCAGACAGCAUUCUAGGAACCAGAGGGAAUGCUGCUGGAAGCUCACAGACAGGUGAUGCACUUGGAAAGGCUUUGGCAUCUAUUUAUUCUCCUGACCAUACCAGCAGUAGUUUUCCGUCAAAUCCAUCAACACCAGUUGGAUCACCUUCACCUCUCACAGGUACCAGUCAGUGGCCAAGACCUGGAGGGCAAGCACCUUCAUCCCCAAGCUAUGAAAACUCACUCCACUCCCUGCAGUCUCGAAUGGAGGAUCGUUUAGACAGACUGGAUGAUGCAAUCCAUGUGCUGCGGAACCAUGCUGUGGGACCUUCCACCAGUUUGCCUGCUGGUCACAGUGAUAUACAUAGUUUAUUGGGACCAUCCCAUAAUGCACCAAUUGGAAGCCUCAAUUCAAACUAUGGAGGAUCAAGCCUUGUUGCAAGCAGUCGAUCAGCUUCAAUGGUUGGAACUCAUCGGGAAGACUCUGUCAGUCUCAAUGGCAAUCAUUCAGUCCUGUCUAGUACAGUCACUACUUCAAGCACAGACCUGAACCAUAAAACACAAGAAAAUUAUAGAGGUGGCUUGCAAAGUCAGUCUGGAACUGUUGUUACAACAGAAAUCAAGACUGAAAACAAAGAAAAGGAUGAAAACCUUCAUGAACCUCCUUCAUCAGAUGACAUGAAGUCAGAUGAUGAAUCCUCCCAAAAAGAUAUCAAGGUUUCAUCUAGAGGCAGAACAAGCAGUACUAAUGAAGAUGAGGAUUUGAACCCUGAACAGAAGAUAGAAAGGGAGAAGGAGAGGCGGAUGGCUAACAAUGCCAGAGAACGCUUACGCGUGCGGGAUAUUAAUGAAGCAUUCAAAGAGCUUGGCCGAAUGUGUCAGCUUCACUUGAAGAGUGAAAAACCCCAAACAAAACUCCUUAUUCUUCAUCAAGCCGUGGCAGUCAUCCUUAGUCUAGAACAGCAAGUCAGAGAGAGGAACCUUAACCCCAAAGCAGCCUGCCUUAAGAGAAGGGAAGAAGAAAAAGUUUCUGCCGUAUCGGCAGAGCCGCCAACCACACUGCCAGGAACCCAUCCUGGGCUUAGUGAAACUACCAACCCUAUGGGUCAUAUGUAAACAUCAGCCAGUUCCAGAGUUAUCAGUAGGCUAGAUAGAAGGUGACCUCUCCUCAUAAGGACUUGGACAACUCAGAUUAUCUGAAGACACAAACCUGACAGGAGGGAGAAGAAAAAACAAAACACUUGAACCAAGAAACUCAAAUGUAAUCCUACGAUCAAAGCAACUGGUCAACACUUCCAUCAGAAGUGAAGAUAGGAAGCUCAUCAGAUAGAACAUCAGCCCAUGAGAUGUUUGCAACAAAUCUUUUGUUGCAAGCAGUGUGUCGCUUCUGCACAAUCAGAGACUGUCUCGAUCUCUCCACUCACCGUGGAAGUUGCCUUGUGCCUAAACUGAAUUGACAAAUGCAUUGUAACUACAAAUUUUAUUUAUUGUUAUGAAACUGUAAGGUCUACAUAUAAAGGGAAAAAGUUAAUGUGGAAAGCUGAUCUACACUCAGCUGAUGCCAGCAUACAUUAAAGCGGUUCACGUGCAGAGAACAAAGCAGUGACAACCAUUGGCCCUUAGCAUUCCCGGCAUACCUAUUAGUGUCUUAAAAAGGAAGGGAAAAGUCUUUUGUUGCCCUCUCCUAUCCUCUUGCCAUAUGAAUAGCGUUUUCCAUGAAAUAGGAAAAUAUUACUUGGUAUAGCAUUUCUCUUGCUCUCAUUUUUUGAUUUAUUUUUAUUUUCUCUUUGUGGGUGUUAUAUUUGAUCUCUAAAUCUGAACAGUUUAUGGUCACAGUCCAGCCUCCUCCGUGCAGCCCUGUGUGCUUUGCACAUUUACCUUACAGUGGUAAGCAGAGACCAUCUGUGACCAUAGCCUAGCUAGCAUUUUAAAAGGGGAAAUUUUGUUCUCUAGGUUUUCCCCCAAAUAAACAUUGCUUUAUUUCUAAUAAUAACCAAGACUUUUCAAGCUUCUAGAUCUCAUAGGAAAGCUUGUAAUAGCAAAAUUGUAAAUUACAAGGGAAGAAUCUACUUUUUAGAAAUCGCUUUGUUUUCCAAGCAGUAAGUACUACAUACAGUACUUGUAAAGUGUUAGCUGUAAGUAAGCACAAAAUACAUUUAAAAUACAAAGACGAUUUUUUCAGGCUGUGAUUAUGGUGAACAUAACAAAACCCAGUAGUCACCAAGGCAGGUAGUGUGAUAAAUGAACACACCACUCUGAGGCUAAUUACCUAAUGGAAUACAAGAGCAAUGGUCACCCGUAUUUCCUUAUCCUAGCCUUUAUUUCUCUGUCAUUUGGAUGGCUGGUCAAUGGGGAAGAAUUGAGUGGGUGAUUUAAUCAACUGCAAACCAUCUGCCCCUGUCCCAAAAUGAUGAGCCAGAUUAGCAUUAAACCAGUACUUGUCAGUCCAUCUUAAUACUGUUCAUUAAGGCACUCUCUGUCUCUAAUCCUUAGGAGUUGUUUUAAAAGACAUAAUCACUUUGAACUUCCAUGAAACCUGUCUUCCACCACAACAACCCUGGGAGAGAAAAACAUGCUAAAGGAGGUAUCUUGGCUUAAUAAUUCCUUAUAGCCAAUAUCAACAGUGGCAAUCAGCACACAGAGGAAAGGACCCAAAUCACUAUGUAGCUUAAAGAUUUCUGUUAAUUUGAAAGAACAAAAACAAGACAGAACUUCUGGUACUCUAAUCAGGAUGAUUCCUAACAAGUCAGUCAUUUGUGAACUUAGUGGACUUUUUGGUUACUUUAAUUUGCAUAUAUUCUCCAGUUACAUCGGACUCUAUCUGUGGCCUUGUUCUUCAUUUCAGUGUUAAUCAGCUAAACAGAAGUUGUUGCUUAUGAUGUGUGAGUGAACAUAUGCCACUGCCUGGCCUUUUUUUCUUCAGAGCUUGUUGUCUUUUUCGCUAUAUUAGACUUUGCAGUAUGCCCAGAAGCUUUCCUUCAUAAAAUAGAAAGAAAAAAACAUUUGGCUUAUUUUUCACUGUAGCUAGUCUUUUAUACAAUAAUCUUGUAAGAAAAUUUCUUGAAUUCUAAAUAUUACUCUUUCUAGAUUUUUGAAAUCAAAAAGUUUUCAGUAAAAAGUUUCUUACUUUAUUUUAUUAUAUUAGGUAGUAAAAAAUGUAGGGUUAUUUACCAUAACCUGUUCAUUAAUAUCAGAAAUUUACAAUAGCAUUUUAAGACCAUAGUAGGAUUCUAGCAUACCGUGUAGUACCUAUGGAGUAUUGUAAGAGCUAAUUGUUGGAGAUGAAUUGCUUCUCAUCUUGUUCUCCAGUUUCCAUUGUUGGUUUAUUGCAGAUUUGUAUCCUGUGUCAAAUUCAAGGUAUUAUUGAUAAACCUUUUCAACCAGCAGCAAGAAGUUCAAAUUUUUUUCUGUCACUGUAACAGAAAACACAAUAUGUAUAUAACAUUUAUGUAGCAAUAAAUGUGCCAUCUUUUUUUUAACACAGUAAAAUAGUGAGUUUUUUACAUUUCUCUUUCUCAAAUAAUAAUGUAUUUUGUUUUAUUUUCUCCAUCUCAUUCGUCCCAGAAACACUCACACUGCUUUUCCUAACUGCAUUACCGACAUUAUCUGGGAAACCCUUCAGGACAGAAUCAGGCUUGUGGAGCUAAGUUGGCAAUCUGGUCUAGAGCUUCUCUAGCUUGUGCUUUUCUCCUCUUGCCCUCACUACUGACGGUGGCCUUUUAACCUUUUCCUAAAGAUUGACCAAACAGCAACUAGUAGUUAUAGAAAAUCUACUCAUUUGUAGAUACAGAGAAAAAUGAAGAAGAUGGAAAAAGACUCAAAAGAGGCUUUUUAAGUUAUUCUUCAAAGCACUUUUCACAUUUCCCCAUACCCUUUCUCACAAAAAAAGUGUCAUAAUUAAGUAAUGGUAUUGUUUACUGUUUAAAAGUUAAAAGAUCAAAAAUUUGCUUUUAUCCCAGUUUUUAACCACAAAAAAAAGCGUAGGGAUUAUCCAUGAGGACUUCAUGCCAAGCAAGAACCUCAAACAAACUAGACAAACUUUUUUUUUGACAGUGAAUGACUUUUUGUAGGACCUGUGCGUGCGAAACCCAUGGCAAUUGUCACAUCCUCUUGGUAUGCUGGCAGAUUGCUUCUCUUGGUGAAUUAUGAAAUCCACUGUUCACAUUGGGUGCCUAACAGAACAUUUUGCUUCUUGUGGGAUUUAGUGAAAACUAUUAAACUUGUUAAGUUGAUUUUAUACAAAACGAUAAAUAAAAAGCUCUAAGAAGAAAAUGUAUAAUCUUAGAGCUGAAAUAAAAUAUAGAGACCAUCUAGUAAAUGACCUCAUUAAUAUAUCUGUGAAAACUGAGACUCAGAUUGUAUGUCUCUAAGAACACAUAAUUAGUAACAGAUCAAGACACUUAAAACUUUCCCUACAAAACCUCCCUGCCUUGACUUUCUCUUUCUCUUUGCAGAUUUCUAGGCCGCUUCUGCUCAGUGUCUUCAUUUUCUUCCAUAUUUGUUUUAUUUCAUUUUUCUUUUCUAUAGUUCAUGUUUUCUUUUUCCUUGGAAACUCAAAAUUUAAACACACGUCGUGUGUGUGUGUGUGUGUGUGUCUGUGUGUGUGUGACUUAAAGAAUCUUAAGCUUUGGCAUUAAAUAGUCCUCGAUUCAAAUCUAAGCUCAACAUCUGAUUAACUUCAUUUUCCUAUCUGAAAAAUGGAGAUAACAUUAGAAUUGUGUAAGUAUUGAAUGAAACAAUGUAUGGAAAGCUCUUAUGGUUCUUGUCACCUAAGAAGUACUUAAUAAAUGAUAAAUAUUUUUAAAUAAAUAAUAUUAUAACCAA